AGCCUCGCUCUGGUCCCUGCGGCUGGCGGCCGAGCCGUGUGUCUCCUCCUCCAUCGCCGCCAUAUUGUCUGUGUGAGCAGAGGGGAGAGCGGCCGCCGCCGCUGCCGCUUCCACCACAGCUCUAUCAAGGCUUGUCAAGCAGUGUGCUCAUCACAUGGUAAAUCAUGCAGCGUGGAACCUCAUAAAAUCUCCAAGAAACAUCAUUCACCCAUACUGACUAGUUUCACAUCUCUUUGUUUGAAGAAAACAGGUCUGAAACAAGGUCUUACCCCCAGCUGCUUCUGAACACAGUGACUGCCAGAUCUCCAAACAUCAAGUCCAGCUUUGUCCGCCAACCUGUCUGACAUGUCGGGACCCGUGCCAAGCAGGGCCAGAGUUUACACAGAUGUUAAUACACACAGACCUCGAGAAUACUGGGAUUACGAGUCACAUGUGGUGGAAUGGGGAAAUCAAGAUGACUACCAGCUGGUUCGAAAAUUAGGCCGAGGUAAAUACAGUGAAGUAUUUGAAGCCAUCAACAUCACAAAUAAUGAAAAAGUUGUUGUUAAAAUUCUCAAGCCAGUAAAAAAGAAGAAAAUUAAGCGUGAAAUAAAGAUUUUGGAGAAUUUGAGAGGAGGUCCCAACAUCAUCACACUGGCAGACAUUGUAAAAGACCCUGUGUCACGAACCCCCGCCUUGGUUUUUGAACACGUAAACAACACAGACUUCAAGCAAUUGUACCAGACGUUAACAGACUAUGAUAUUCGAUUUUACAUGUAUGAGAUUCUGAAGGCCCUGGAUUAUUGUCACAGCAUGGGAAUUAUGCACAGAGAUGUCAAGCCCCAUAAUGUCAUGAUUGAUCAUGAGCACAGAAAGCUACGACUAAUAGACUGGGGUUUGGCUGAGUUUUAUCAUCCUGGCCAAGAAUAUAAUGUCCGAGUUGCUUCCCGAUACUUCAAAGGUCCUGAGCUACUUGUAGACUAUCAGAUGUACGAUUAUAGUUUGGAUAUGUGGAGUUUGGGUUGUAUGCUGGCAAGUAUGAUCUUUCGGAAGGAGCCAUUUUUCCAUGGACAUGACAAUUAUGAUCAGUUGGUGAGGAUAGCCAAGGUUCUGGGGACAGAAGAUUUAUAUGACUAUAUUGACAAAUACAACAUUGAAUUAGAUCCACGUUUCAAUGAUAUCUUGGGCAGACACUCUCGAAAGCGAUGGGAACGCUUUGUCCACAGUGAAAAUCAGCACCUUGUCAGCCCUGAGGCCUUGGAUUUCCUGGACAAACUGCUGCGAUAUGACCACCAGUCACGGCUUACUGCAAGAGAGGCAAUGGAGCACCCCUAUUUCUACACUGUUGUGAAGGACCAGGCUCGAAUGGGUUCAUCUAGCAUGCCAGGGGGCAGUACGCCCGUCAGCAGCGCCAAUAUGAUGUCAGGGAUUUCUUCAGUGCCAACCCCUUCACCCCUUGGACCUCUGGCAGGCUCACCAGUGAUUGCUGCUGCCAACCCCCUUGGGAUGCCUGUUCCAGCUGCCGCUGGCGCUCAGCAGUAACGGCCCUAUCUGUCUCCUGAUGCCUGAGCAGAGGUGGGGGAGUCCACCCUCUCCUUGAUGCAGCUUGCGCCUGGCGGGGAGGGGUGAAACACUUCAGAAGCACCGUGUCUGAACCGUUGCUUGUGGAUUUAUAGUAGUUCAGUCAUAAAAAAAAAAUUAUAAUAGGCUGAUUUUCUUUUUUCUUUUUUUUUUUAACUCGAACUUUUCAUAACUCAGGGGAUUCCCUGAAAAAUUACCUGCAGGUGGAAUAUUUCAUGGACAAAUUUUUUUUUCUCCCCUCCCAAAUUUAGUUCCUCAUCACAAAAGAACAAAGAUAAACCAGCCUCAAUCCCGGCUGCUGCAUUUAGGUGGAGACUUCUUCCCAUUCCCACCAUUGUUCCUCCACCGUCCCACACUUUAGGGGGUUGGUAUCUCGUGCUCUUCUCCAGAGAUUACAAAAAUGUAGCUUCUCAGGGGAGGCAGGAAGAAAGGAAGGAAGGAAAGAAGGAAGGGAGGACCCAAUCUAUAGGAGCAGUGGACUGCUUGCUGGUCGCUUACAUCACUUUACUCCAUAAGCGCUUCAGUGGGGUUAUCCUAGUGGCUCUUGUGGAAGUGUGUCUUAGUUACAUCAAGAUGUUGAAAAUCUACCCAAAAUGCAGACAGAUACUAAAAACUUCUGUUCAGUAAGAAUCAUGUCUUACUGAUCUAACCCUAAAUCCAACUCAUUUAUACUUUUAUUUUUAGUUCAGUUUAAAAUGUUGAUACCUUCCCUCCCAGGCUCCUUACCUUGGUCUUUUCCCUGUUCAUCUCCCAACAUGCUGUGCUCCAUAGCUGGUAGGAGAGGGAAGGCAAAAUCUUUCUUAGUUUUCUUUGUCUUGGCCAUUUUGAAUUCAUUUAGUUACUGGGCAUAACUUACUGCUUUUUACAAAAGAAACAAACAUUGUCUGUACAGGUUUCAUGCUAGAGCUAAUGGGAGAUGUGGCCACACUGACUUCCAUUUUAAGCUUUCUACCUUCUUUUCCUCCGACCGUCCCCUUCCCUCACAUGCCAUCCAGUGAGAAGACCUGCUCCUCAGUCUUGUAAAUGUAUCUUGAGAGGUAGGAGCAGAGCCACUAUCUCCAUUGAAGCUGAAAUGGUAGACCUGUAAUUGUGGGAAAACUAUAAACUCUCUUGUUACAGCCCCGCCACCCCUUGCUGUGUGUAUAUAUAUAAUACUUUGUCCUUCAUAUGUGAAAGAUCCAGUGUUGGAAUUCUUUGGUGUAAAUAAACGUUUGGUUUUAUUUAUCAAGGUUAGAUUUAAGUUCCCUGUGUAAAGGUCUUGCUGGGUGGGUGUCUCAUGUUCACAUCUGAGGGGCCUGCAGCCCUGUACCGUGGAGGCUUCCCAAGGCCCCCAUUUUAUACACCCCUCGUUCGACCCAUGGUACCGGGCAGAGCAGAGAGGCCUUAAAAAAAAAGCACCACAAGCCAAAGCGUCUCUGGGGAUUAAGGAUCCUUUGCCAUAAAACUCAUUUUGUGUCUCAGCAGUGCAGGGAUUGGGGAUGGAAAAAGUCGCCAGUUUUUGUGUGUUUGUGUGUGUGUGUAAAGUGGACUUUCCACUGUAAUCCAACCACCUAAGUUUAUCAGGUGCUUCACUGAGGAAGCCUAGUUUUUUAAGCACAAUAGCAAAACCAUCAGCUCUGUAUUUUCUCCUGUUAUUUCAUUACAGUAGCUGCUUGUGGGAACUAGGAAAAAUUCUUCCAACAUAUUUUAAGGCCUAAAAUCUUAGUUCCCCAUUCUCCUACCUUAUAGAUUCACAGGCCUUUCUCGCCUAGGCAUCAUAGAUAAACGUAAUUGUUUGGGGAGUUGAAUUUAAUGAACUUAUCUAACUUUGUAACCCAUCUUGGCUUUAGUAACUUUAUCAAGGUGGUGGCUUUAGUGAAUAUAAUGGUAAACUUUAGAGGACGCUAAAGCCUCCUUUUAUAGCGCUUCUCAACGGUAGGGAGAGCUGAAGGGAAAACAUUCUGACUGUGUGGCAGGGUGAUUUUCUUCCUUAUGACCACUUACAGUGGAUAUUUAUUGUACUUGACCCUUUUAUGCCCUAGAAUGCUGUGAGGGUUACCAUGUUGAAUUUGUGCAGAAGCUAAAAGCACCAGAUGUGCCAGAGAUGCAAUUUGUGAUUAUGUUUGCACUGGAUUGUGAUUUGAACAGGACACUUAUAACUAAUGAGUUCUUUCUUUUGAGGUGGGGAGAGGGUUGUAAAUCAAGACUUCAUACCCUAUCCUUGUAGCUCGGAAAUUGAGGUGUAGCUUAGGCUGAUGCGGAGAGCUGCAGACAGCUGGACCUCCUUACACCCAUCAGACCUUGGAAUAAACCGAAGGUGAAUGCAGAGGACUCUGAGGUGCCACCCAAGAGCCUUUUAAAAUAAAUAGAAGUUUUUAAAAAUGCUACUUAAGAGUCACUGCAGAAGCAUGGAGAGAGAGAAAAAAAAAAAAGACCCAAUUGGGUGGGGGGUGGGGGGGAGGCAAGGGUUUACAGAGUAACAACUUACGUGUUGUUGUAAAUUACCUCAUCUGUAUACCUUGUAUUGGGACACUAUUUCUCAGCACUACCUGUGUCUGCAUUGCUUAGAUGGCAGGAAAUGGAAUGGCCAACAUGAAAGGUUAUGUUGGCAAUUACUCUGAAAGAUUUUUUAAAGUAUUUUUAAACUUUGUUUGAAGUGGUCCCUCCCCUCUUCCUCUGCUUUUUUUUAAGUUUGAAGCCAGAAGGCCCUCCCCACCUUGCUUUAUUGGUUGUAAUUGUAUUGUAAUUGGUAUGACUAAACCAUAACUGUGCUGGGAAGAAGUUGUGCCAUGAAGGUCUUUAAUUUUUUUUAAUAAAAACAUUUAAAUAAAUGAAAUGUCCCUGCAGCCUGAGCAAUAUGCUUCUCCAACCGACACCGUGUGUGAUAGAUGGCUCCGUUUUCACGUUUUGAAUUCUGUUUCUUGUACUUGAAAUGCCUGUCCAGCUUACAUAAGAUAGAUUAAAUUGUUAGAGUGGGACUGUCAGAGGAAUAUAUCUUGUAAAGUAGAUCCUCAGGGUAUGGCUAAUUACUAUAGUCCUAAAGUAGCAGAGAAAAUUAGAGAUUGGUUGACAGAUUUGGGAAUUUUAAUUUCUUCUUAGUUUUUAACUUUCAUCUUUGCUUCACCUUUUGACAAGUAUGGUUAUAAUUAGAAUUGACCAUUUAAGCAUCUCUUGAAAAACCUGAUUUUGUCCCACCAGCAAAUUCUCUCCCAAGACUGGAAUUGGGUUUGCAUAGUAGAGAGCCUGUCUUCCCAGGGCCUUUUCCUAGUUAAAGAAACACUUAACUAAAAAGGCUGUGUGGUAAGGUCAUGCUCAGUUCCUUCCUCAAAAAAUGAGUCUAAAAUUGGUUUAUCCUGAAUCCGACUUCCCCCACUGUCAUCACUUACCCUUGCCCUUCUUUUUCCUCAGAACACCUGAACUUUUGUUGUAUUAUUUUGUAUCUCCCCACUUGCAUGUAAACUCCCUGGUGACCUUGCAUGUCUUAUGCAAUCCUCAUUAAAACCUUUUGUUUUUUUUUUUAAGUGGGUUCGUUUUCCCUCAGGAUCGAAGAGUAUUGAAUGGAAUGGCACGAGGAAAAUAUUUAACACCCUACUUGGCUUGUAAUAAUAGGUGCUUAAUAAAUUGUAGUUCCACUCUCCACUCCAUUGCCCCCUUUCUCUCCCUACACACACACACCCACCCACCCACACACACACACACACACACACAAAGUAAAUGGAAGUAUUGUUGCAUAAAGAGCAUCUCAAAAUCCUAAGAACUUUGCCCUUGAGUUUGCAGCUAUAAUUACAAGCCACAGGCCAGACUGAACUAACAUGACAAGUAACUUUAUUUAAUGAGACCCUGAUAAAUAGGUAUCUGAAGACUAAGGAAUGAUCCUGGCCAAUUUAGUAGACUUAGAUGCUGCAGUCUCCCUGCUUUUCCCCUGCUGUAUUACCUGUGUGUAAUAUAGGUUGAAUAUCCCCUAUCCAAAAUGGUUGGGACCAGAAGUGUUUUGAAUUUUUUUGGAUUUUUGGAAUAUUUGCGGAAUACAUACCAGUUCAAUAUUCCUAAUCUGAAAUUUGAAAUAUUCCAAAUAGCAUUUACUUUAGGCAUCAUGUUGAUGCUUAAAAAAUUUCAGAUUUUUGAGGAUUUUGUAUUUUCAAAUUAGAAAUGCUCAACGUGUAAUACGAAAUUCAGACUAUUCUCCAAGUAAAACAUAUGUAGAUGGUGUCACAAGAUGUUCUGGACUCAAUCCUAUGUAAAUAAGUACUUCCUAGACUUUAUAGCUCUCCUUUGAUUCUGUGCUAAAUUUAACCAUUAGAGAAGCAAUGUAAUGUUACUGCAAGUGGUCUACCUCUAACAGAGUUCUGUCUGGCAGUGUGAUUUUUUUGAUCAGUUAACCUCUCUGAAUCUUUUCUUCACAGGUGAUUUAAAUUGUUAUUGUAAAACAUUUUAGGCAUGUACCAAAUUAUAAAGAAAGCUGUAACACAUCCAUAAUCCUACCACCCAAGUUGAAUUUCCAUUGCCAAUACAGACCAAGCCCCCUUUUUGCCCUUUUUUGGUGAUACCCUCUUCUUCCUCCCUUCCCCAGAGGUCCCAAUAUUUCCUAUCUGUUAAAUUGGGGUAUAAGUACUGAUUUCAUAGAGCGGUUGUUCAGAUUCUAUGACAGAUGCCUGGUAUAUGGUAGAGUUACACCAAAUGUUGGUUUCUCUUCUAAAUUGUACAGUUGUGCAGACUAUGUACAGUAAAAGGAUGCUACAUUAUAGGGAGGCCAUAGAUGUUUGCAUUUGGAAAAUUUCUGACUCUUUUCCAGCAGGUGGCAGUAAAGUGUCUUUACUAGAAGAAAAAAUAUCCAAGCAUUAAACAUGACAGGUUUUCAACGGGUACAAGUCAAGUUUCUGAUUGAAUGAAGGCCAGCAUUGCCUUGUUCCCACUCCCUCUAUGGAAAGCCAGAUAUUUUGCACUGUAGCAAAUUACAAACUGGAUUUGUCUCCCUGUCGCUCUACUCACUAGAAGUUUUUUGUUUGUUUUGUUUUUUGAUACGGGUCUUGCUCUGUUACCCAGGCUAGAGUGCAGUAGCGCCAUCACAGCUCACUGCAGCCUCAACCUCCCAGGCUCAGGUGAUCCUCCCAACUCAGCCUUCCAGGGACUACAGGCACGAGCCAUCAUGCUUGGCUAAUUUUUUUUUUUUUUUUUUUGGUAGAGAUGAAGUUUUGCCGUGUUGCCCAGGCUGGUCUUGAACUCCUGAGCUCAACAGUCUACCCGCCUUGGCCUCCCAAAGUGCUGAGAUUAGAGGCAUGAGCCACCACACCUGGCCCACUAGGGAUUCUUAUUGGCCUCAAUGUGAGAAGCCCUUCCCCAGGUACCUCCAGAUGGAAGCUUACAGGAUGGUCAGUCCAUUUCUUAGAGAAGUUCCUGGGGGGAUUGAGUAUUUCUGAGUCAGCUUCACUCUUGCAUCAUCUGCUUUGACAGUUUUCUUGGCUCCUGUAAUGAGAAAAAGGGAAAAAAAUGCUGCAGCAGCUGGGGCUGGCUUCCUGAUCCCACCCUGGGAAUCAGAGUCUCAGCUAUUGAUAAACAUUUCUAGCCAUACCUAGAAGGAGAGGACCUUGCUUCUGUGUGUUGAACAGUUCCAAGAACUCCAUGGUGAACUUCCUAUGAAGAACCCUCCAUAACCCUCAACCCUUCAAACCUGACGGUAUACCUCAUUUUGUUCUCCCGUCUCUGGCAUUCCUCACCCACCCACGCUGACUGGUCUUUCCAAAGUUCAUUUCUGUAAUAUAGGAUGUCUUUGGUUUCAACAAACAUUUGUAAGUGCCCCUGAGCCUGGUCUUUGCUAUACACUGGGGAUUGAGAGGUGAGACACAAGCCCAUGGGGAAAUGUAUGUUAAUUAGAAAAGUGAAAAAAUUGUGUAUAUGGGAUAAUUCCAACUGUUUUAAAAAAAAAAUCCUAGGAAAAAUGCAAAUGCCUAUUUCAGAGAAAGAAAUGGAAAUCCCAAGGUGGCAAAAAGGAAGGCAGAAUUCAUCCUGAAUGUAACUGGGGUUUUUUUGUUUUGUUUUGUUUUGUUUGUUUGUUUUGUUUUUGAGACAGGCAUGGGAUUACAUGCACCACCACGCCCAGCUAAUUUUGUAUUUUUAGUAGAGACGGGGUUUCUCCAUGUUGGUCAGGCUGGUCUCGAACUCCCGACCUCAGGUGAUCCGCCCGCCCAAGCCUCCCAAAGUGGUGGGAUUACAGGCGUGAGCCACUGCGCCCAGCCUAAGUGGGUAUUAAAGUCAGUGCUUCCAAGACACUGGGUCUGGGUAUAGGUGGGCCUCAGGCUAUGGACUAGGGUUUGAAUGCCCCCAGGGAGAUAGGACACAGACUCCCGGGCUUUCUAAGAUAGAAACUGAAACAAUGCUGUGGCACUUGGAAAGGCUACAGGGGCAGGAUUGAGGUGGUGGGGGUGGUAAAAACUAGAAGAAUACUAGCUGUUGUUGCCUCUGGGUGAUGAGGUUAAGAUACCACGGAAGGCCCACACACCUGUGGUUGGAACACUUUGGGAGCCGGGAGUCCCAGACCAGCCUGGACAACAUGGCGAAAACCCACCUCUACAAAAAAUAGAUUAGCUGAGUGUGGUGGUGUGCGCCUGUGUCCUAGCUACUGGGGAGGCCAAAGGACGAGAAUUAAUUGCCUGAGCCCAAGAAGUCAAGGCUGCAGUGAGGUGUGAUUGUGCCACAGUACUCAAGCCCAAGUGACAGAGCAAGACCCUGUCUAAAAAGAUUUUUUUAAAGUCACAGAAGCUGGGCGUGGUGGCUCAUGCCUGUAAUCUCAGCUCUUUGGGAGGCUGAGGCAGGAGGAUUGCUUGAGGCCACGAGUUGGAGACCAGCCUGGGCAACAUAGGGAGACCCUGUCUCUACCAAAAUUAAAAAUUAGCUGGAUGUGGUGGCACAUGCCUGUAGUGCUAGCUACUCUGGAGGCUGAGGCAGGAGGAUCACUUGAGCCCAGGGGUUCAAGGCUGCAGUGAGCUAUGAUAGUGCCACUGCACCCCAGACUGAGCAACAGAGUGAGACCCUGUCUGUAAAAGAAGUUGUUAUUAAUUGAAAAAAAGAUUUAACAGGCUGGGUGCAGUGGCUCACACCUGUAAUCUCAGCACUUUGAGAGGUGGAGGCGGGCGACUCACUUGAGCUCAGGAAUUCAAGGCCGGUCUGGGAAACAUGAUGAAACCCUCUCUACAAAAAAUACACAGAUUAGCUGGGCAUGGUGGUGCAUGCCUGUAGUCCCAGCUACUUGGGAGGCUGAGAUGGAGGAAUCAAUUGAGCCCAGGAGGUUGAGGCUGCAGUGAGCCAUGAUUUCACCACUGCACUCCAGCCUGUGCAACAUAGGGAGACCCCGCCUCCAAAAAAAAAAGUAACAGAAAAACUCACUAGGUGCCGGGCAUGGUGGCUCACGCCUGUAAUCCAACACUUUGGGAGACCAAGGCGAGUGGAUCACCUGAGGUCAGGAGUUUGAAACCAGACUGAACAACAUGGUGACACCCUGUUUCUACUAAAAAAUACAAAAAUUAGCUGGGCUUGGUGACGUGUGCCUGCAGUCCCAGCUACUUGGGAGGCUGAGGCAGGAGAAUUGCUUGAGCCUGGGAGGUGGCGGUUACAGUGAGCUGAGAUCACGUCAGUGUACUCCAGCCUGGGUGACAGAGCCAGACUCCAUCUAAAAGUAAAAAAGAAAAACUCACUAGGAAGGAAUCUUGAAGUCUUGGAGAAGAGAGAAUGGUCCAUGAGGCCUCAGAGGAGGGGCUGCCUGAACUGGCGAGGGAGAGGCCCAGCCUAACAAGUUUCAGCUGCCAAGGCCCAUGCCUGGGAUCAGAACCCUGUCUCCUGGCUCAAUUUUGCUUGUGGGGCUGCUUUUGCACAGCUAUGUUGCCAGGAAUCUGUCCAGGUUCCUAGCCAGUCAUUGCAGACAAAUUUUUUCUUUCUUUUGCUUUUGUUCUCUGUCUAGUCUUAGUCUCACAAAUUUCUAAGGCAACUGUAUGUAGUUCAGCUGAUCUAGAUCAAGUUCAGCCCAAGCAGCUGUUUUUCAGGUUGUGGGUCGGCUGGGCUGGACACCUCCAUGUGAAUUGGAUUCAGGUUUGCCCAAUGUGGCAGAAGUUGCAGCAGCUACUCAGGGCGUGCUCUUCUCAUGAAUCACAGAAACUUAGAAGAGACCAAAUGGAAUCACACAAGCACAUUUCAAGCCUCUGCUGUGUCACAAGCACCAUCAUCCCAUUGGCGAAAGCAAAUCACAUAGCCAAGCCCAACAUCAGUGCAGUAGGGAAGCAUAGAGCCUGUGUUGGGAAAACUUUAUGAGGUUAUAUGGCAAAGGGUGUGUAUGUUUAGUCUUAUUACAGGGGAAUGAAGAAACAAACCAAUAAUGCAAUCAGCCAUACUAUUCAUAUAUAUCAGUAGGAACAGAAGGCAACCACAUAUAACAUCUAUGUAUAUAUAUAUGUGUGUGUGGAAAGGAUUACACCAACUUUUUUUUUUUUUUUUUGAGUCAGAGUCUUAACUCUGUCACCCAGGCUGGAGUGCGGUGGCAUGAUCUCAGCCCACUGCAACCUCCACCUCCCAGGUUCAAGCGAUUCUCCUGCCUCAGCCUCCCAAGUAGUUGGGAUUAUAGGCACAUGCCACCACACCCAGAUAGUUUUUGUAUUUUUACAAAACAACAGGGUUUCACCAUGUUGGCCAGGCUGGUCUGGAACUCCUGACAUCAAGUAAUCUGCCUGCCUCGGCCUCCAAAAGUGCUGAGAUUAUAGGCGUGAGCCACCGUGCCCGGCUGAGAAUACUUGUUUACUUGUUUUCAAGCAACAAAAAUUGAGAAUCAGUCUUUGAGACUCCAUGGCCAGAAACAACACAACAUUCCACUAUACACAGGGUGCUUCUGGGGGUCCUCGGUGUUGUGUUUAUUGGGGUGGUACCUAAAUGUUGUAUUUGCUCUAUAAUUAUUUGUUAAACUCUCCAUUUACGUUUGGGGCACUUCUCAGUAUAUUUGCUAGAGUUCAAAUGUUUAAAAGUUUACAAAAUGAAAACUGAGCAGAGUAAGACAAGCCAAAAAAGUAUUAACUCAGCAGGAAUGGGAAAAGUUAUGAAAGGAGGGAAAACUAAAUAUCAUACUGCUGGUUCAGCUGUGAUUAGAAUUUACGUAGUCAUAAUGGAAACACUGAAUACUGGUCUAACCAGGAUUACAGUAUGAUGACAAUGGAAAGAGGAGUGAUGGGAAAUGCUGGCAUGUGUGGUGGUGUUGGUAACAGGACAAGCGGUCUAAGCUCUAAACUCUCAUCAUUUAUAAGGGGAACUAAUGCCUAAAACUGAAAAAUCAAACAGUUGCAUGUUAUUUUGAGAUUUUUUAAAUUAUUGUUAAGAUAGUAGCAGUAUUUACUUUUAAAACUAUAUUUAUGUAUUACUCUGGUGAAAAAGCAACUACUUUUAAUAAAUGGAUAUUUAUCUUGAAUGCAUCCACUUCCUCCCAUUCCCGUUGCCAAAUUCCUCAUCCCAGCCACCAUCCUCUCUUGCUUGGAGUAUCAUAGCAGAUAACUGGUCUUGAUGCCUUCCCAUCUCGUCUCAAUUCCUGAUUCAUCUGACACCUGCAACCAAAGAUCUUUCAAAAAUAAAUAUUCUAGUCCAGGCACAGUGACUCAUAUCUAUAACCCCAGCAUUUUGGGAGGCCAAGGCCCGAUGAUCACUUGAGGCCUGGGUAACACAGCGAGUCCUCUGUUCUACAAAAAAUGAAAACAUUAACUAGUGUGGUGGUGUGUGACUAUAGUGCUAGCUACUGGGGAGGCUGGGUGGGAGGAUACGUUGAGCCCAGGAGUUGGAGGCUGCAGUGAGCUAUGAUCACAUUGCUCUCAGUGAGACCUGGCUGACAGAGUGAGAACCUCUCUCUUAAAAAUAAUAAAUAAAUUUUAUCUCAGUCCCUUGCUUAAAAGCCUUUCAAAGACUAGAUCACUUGCAAUGUUGUUGUCUCCUCCCAAGGGAGUCAUUCCUCCCUUCCUCUUUGUUGACAGAGCCCCAGUUUGAGGGACAGCGGGAUAUCCACCAUGCUGCUGUGAGACUCGGGCAGUUGUGACUGGUUUAGAAGUGGAUACACAGGGAGAGGUCUUCUGGAAAAGGUCUUCUGGAGAGCUGAGAUCAGAAGACAAUCAACUGGCUUCAAAUCUAAGGAGAGACAGGCACAAAAUGGAAGAGAUGACAUGGGCACUGGUUACCUGGUAAACACAAGUGGACACUGGUGAGGGACUGGGUCAUGGAGACUGCAGUAGUCUUUACCCUUUUCAGCGUUUUUCACCAUGAACCCCACUGGGAGCACACAGAAGAUUGGAGAAAGUUUUAAUAAAAUGUCUCAAGAUCUGGAAGAAGACAAUGGCAGCUACUGUGAAAGGAUCACAGUGCUCCACCCAGACCCUUCCCUGUAUCCCCUACCGGACAAAAGCCUUAGUCUGUGGAGGGAAGGACACCAAAUCCUGUCACCCCCUUGGAUGAAGCUCCCUUGCAUCUGGGGGAAUGAAACAGGAACAAAACAAAACUUUCCCUGGGCAGGGGCAGGAAUACACACUGGGCCCAGAACUGGGGGAGGAACAGGAGCACUAAGGAGGACAUAACCCCAAAAUCAGAGACACAAAGGGCCUGACAGAGACUGAGACUUGAUCAGAACAGAGAAUUCCCUCCUCCCCCACCUGCCAAUGGUAAGCUGACAAGCCUUGAGUUAGAAGUAAAAAUGUUACAGGAGAGAGACAAGAGUAUGGGAAGAAGACCCUUUCUGAGGGUCACAAAGGGAGGACCUAAAGCUGAGCAGGGAGCACACAUGGAAGGAGAAAAUCCCUCUGGCAGGCCAGCCUGCACCCUCAGUCCAAGGUGUCAUUGGAGGAACUGGAAGCUGCUGCAUUGGGGGUAACCAUAGCAACAAUAAACCUCAAACCUAGCCCAACUCUUUUUUUUAUUUACUUUUUAGAGACAAGGUCUUGCUCUGUUGCCCAGGCUGAAGUGCAGUGGUGUGAUCGCAGCUCACUGCAGCCUCAAACUCCUGGGCUCAAGCAAUCCUCCUGCUUCAGCCUUUGUAGGAGAUUGGUCAGGGUGGUGGGAGAAAUUAUAGGAAAGACACAAACCUUCUUGGAAGGCCGAGAGGUUUUGCAAAAGCUUCAGAAAGAAAUUAUGGCUGAAGGCAGCCAAAUUCUUAUCUGAAGCCUGAGAGCAAAGGGCAGAUAACAGGGGAGUUGUAUAGGAACUUACCUAGAUAAAUUUGUUUAUUCCUGUGUCCAGAAACCAACCUUUGAUCAUUCACACACAGGACUGCUGUCUACUUGGGAUGUUGACAAUGUUUAUUGCCCACAAAUUGUGUUUGCUCCAAGCCUUUGUCAUUAAAUUUGUGCUAAAUAAAUGUGAGGGCCACCAGCUUAAGGGGACUGCUAACUCUCUUCGGCCCCUAGUGCUGGCAGUCCCCUAGCCUGCUCUCUCACUGAA